CAUAAACUUUCCUCUUCCUGCCUAGAGGCCCCACCUUUGGUGCUUUCCAGAAUCCCGUAACACCUGAUUAACUGAGGCAUCCACUUCUUUCAGCAGACUGAUCAGGACCUCCAAGCCACUGAGCAAUGUAUAACCCCAAAGAAAUAAUUUUUAGAAUCUCUUUCGAAGUUUUCCUAAAGUGUAUGGUUUGGGAGUUGUUUGUACUGAGCCAGGUUUGAAAAGGCCAUUGCUGAGUUUGAGGUGGUGCCACCAGUUUUGCAGGUGGCAUCAGAGGCUGGCAUGCUGGCAGGAACAUCCCCUCUUAGCCCCAGUCUUCUCUUUUCUAUAAUGAGACCCACCCCAGCUUGCCUCCCUCCCUGGCUUCUCUGACCCUCAAAGGAGAUGCCACGCAGGACAGACUGGAGAGAGAAGCCUGGGCAAUACUGCCCGCCUGUCAUGGCCUGGUGGUGGCCCACACCUAUCUUCUCACCUUGGAGGCCACACCCAACUUUCCAAAGACCCUGAGACAAGUCAGGACCCUACUACUCUCCCCUGCUGCUUUCCUGACAGCUUACUCUUCCUCCACCUGCUGAGCCUGUGCCAGACUCCAUUGCUCAAAUCGUUAGGGUUGCUUCUAUAAAAAUGGGUCAGUAGCCCUUCCUGUUCUCUCCAGCCCAGCAUACAGGAGGAUCAAAGGAGGUGACGGAGCAUCGUGGCACGGCAGUCUCAAUGGGUCAGAAACCCAGGCCAGCUGGGCUCUAAGCCUGGCAUCCUGUCAUGCUUAGUCCUUCAGCUGAAGAUCAGAGGAAGCCUCUCCCUUGCCCUCUCCAGCUCUAGGGGUUUUCAGGAGGCCCAACUGCAAUAAUGGAGCACUAGUGCUUUUAUGUGCAAUGGUGUCGUCCAUGCACGACAGCAGCAAACAUUCUGGGGCUGCUUUUUAUUGUUCCCACGGCUGACAGCGUGGCAGCGGAGACUGUGGAGGCAGUGGAGACUGACUUCUUCCUGCUGACAGCUGGAUGUCACACAUGAAGGUCUGGCCUAGCGAGUGAUGGGUCUAGGCCCUGAAACUGAUGUCCUAGCAAUAACCUCUUGAUCCCUACUCACCGAGUGUUGAGCCCAAGGGGGGAUUUGUAGAACAAGCCCCCAUGAGAAACAGCUGUUACUCUACACUUUUGAUUGCCUAUUUCUGAUGGCAAGAGAUACAUACUCUCUUCAAAGAGCAUGAGAUGCAGCCAUUCUUUCAGCAAAGCUUCAUUGACACCUGCACCUGUUAACUGUGUUCGACAUUGAAGGGAGAAAGGCAAGAUGUGCACUCUGGACUCAAGAAACUCUUAGUUCAGUGGAGGAAAUGAGCAGAUAAGUAGAUCAUUAUGAUUGAGAGUAGGAGAAGCUUAGAGAAAGCACAGAAUCCCAGAUCCAGCUGGUGAAGGAGGGAAGGCUUCAGGCCUUUAAGCUCAGCCUGAGAAUAUUGUGAAAUGCAGAGGAUGGGGAAAAGGGAAGAGUACCGACUUGAAAACGGAGAGCUGUCUUGGCUGAGGGCAGGGUCUGUGUGGCAGGAUGGGGGAGGGAGUCAGAAGGGUCAGAUGAACUGGAGUGUAGACAGCAUCAGAUGCAGCAGUGCCCACCGCCCCCCCCCCCACCCCCCGCCCUGCCCACAGAGCACCUGCUGGUAACCCUGGGCCUAUUGAAAGCAGGAUGAGAUGAUAAUUUAAGACACUGAAUGAUUUCUUUUCCAACAAAGCUCUAUGUUAAGUGCAUCAAAGAUGUGACAUUGCAUCUUUUACAGGUGAUUCAAGGGUGGGGGAGGCAAGAUGCAGGCAAAGCCACCGUUUCACUGGGUGGAUUCAGUAGGUCCCCCACCCCCAGCAGUUCCCGAAGGUGCUGGGGAGAUUUUUAAAACACCAGUGACAGAAUCUCACCCCCGUAAGUGAUAAAGCCUGAGCAUCAGGAUGAAGUCUCCGCAGGGGGUUCUAAUGUACAGGGUGAGGAUGCUUCAGUUGGCAACGGGAAGCCAUUCAGGUUUCUGAUGGGCUUUUCGGGGGCACGUGGCAGGGAAGAGGGUUUGUGUCACUUUUAGACAAUCAGCUUCUCAGGGGAAACUGUCUGCACUGUGUAUACCAGAAGCUCCACAAAUGUCUCAGGACAUCGAUGACAGCCCCUCAGUAGAAGACCUCCCUGUUCUGGCCCUUCUGCCUUGCCCCCGGAGGUUCCAGCUGUAGUUGAUGAAGCAAAACUUUCCAAGCCAGAGGAGGUGUUACAGUGUCAGGGGAAGCUGAUGGAGAAUCGAGCUCUGGAUCCAGGGACUCGGGACUCCUAUGGUGCCACCAGCCACCUCCCCAACAAGGGGGCCCUGGCGAAGGUCAAGAACAACUUCAAAGACUUGAUGUCCAAACUGACGGAGGGCCAGUAUGUGCUGUGCCGGUGGACAGAUGGCCUGUACUACCUCGGGAAGAUCAAGAGGGUCAGCAGCUCUAAGCAAAGCUGCCUCGUGACUUUCGAAGAUAAUUCCAAAUACUGGGUCCUAUGGAAGGACAUACAGCAUGCCGGUGUUCCAGGAGAGGAGCCCAAGUGCAACAUCUGCCUAGGGAAGACAUCAGGGCCGCUGAAUGAGAUCCUCAUCUGCGGGAAGUGUGGCCUGGGUUACCACCAGCAGUGCCACAUCCCCAUAGCGGGCAGUGCUGACCAGCCCCUGCUCACACCUUGGUUCUGCCGACGCUGCAUCUUCGCACUGGCUGUGCGGAAAGGCGGCGCGCUGAAGAAGGGCGCCAUCGCCAGGACGCUGCAGGCCGUGAAGAUGGUGCUGUCCUACCAGCCCGAGGAGCUCGAGUGGGACUCGCCCCAUCGCACCAACCAGCAGCAAUGCUACUGCUACUGCGGCGGGCCCGGAGAAUGGUACCUGCGGAUGCUGCAAUGUUACCGGUGCAGGCAGUGGUUCCACGAGGCCUGCACCCAGUGCCUCAAUGAGCCCAUGAUGUUUGGAGACCGGUUUUACCUGUUCUUCUGCUCCGUGUGUAACCAGGGCCCAGAGUACAUCGAGAGGCUGCCCCUGCGAUGGGUGGAUGUGGUUCACCUGGCCCUCUAUAAUCUGGGGGUACAGAGCAAGAAGAAGUACUUUGACUUUGAGGAGAUUCUGGCCUUUGUCAACCACCACUGGGAGCUCCUGCAGCUUGGCAAGCUCACCAGCACCCCAGUGACAGAUCGAGGACCACAUCUCCUCAACGCUCUGAACAGUUAUAAAAGCCGGUUCCUCUGCGGCAAGGAGAUCAAGAAGAAGAAGUGCAUCUUCCGCCUGCGCAUCCGCGUCCCACCCAACCCGCCAGGGAAGCUGCUGCCUGACAAAGGACUGCUGCCAAAUGAGAACAGCGCCUCCUCUGAGCUGCGUAAGAGAGGAAAGAGCAAGCCUGGUUUGUUGCCUCACGAAUUCCAGCAGCAGAAAAGGCGAGUUUAUAGAAGAAAAAGAUCAAAGUUUUUGCUGGAAGAUGCUAUUCCCAGUAGUGACUUCACCUCAGCCUGGAGCACCAACCACCACCUGGCUAGCAUAUUUGACUUCACGCUGGAUGAAAUUCAAAGUUUAAAAAGUGCCAGCUCAGGCCAGACCUUCUUCUCAGAUGUCGACUCCACCGACGCUGCCAGCACCUCUGGCUCUGCCUCCACCAGCCUCUCCUAUGACUCCAGAUGGACAGUGGGCAGCCGAAAGAGGAAGCUGGCAGCCAAGGCAUACAUGCCCCUGCGGGCAAAGCGGUGGGCAGCUGAGCUGGAUGGACGCUGCCCCUCGGACAGCAGUGCAGAGGGGGCUUCAGUCCCCGAGCGGCCAGACGAAGGCAUUGACAGCCACACAUUUGAGAGCAUCAGUGAAGAUGACUCAUCCCUGUCCCACCUCAAGUCAUCUAUCACCAACUACUUUGGUGCAGCUGGGCGGUUGGCCUGUGGGGAGAAGUACCAGGUGUUGGCUCGGAGGGUCACACCUGAGGGCAAGGUUCAGUACCUGGUGGAGUGGGAAGGGACCACCCCUUACUGACUAGCCCCCGGGGGUGCCAGGGGUCCUGAAAACCAAAGGAGGAGCAGCAGAAGCCAUAGGCUCCCCAGCUUUCUCCAGGCUGGGGUGGGAGAAGGAAGCAGGACAGAGCUGCAAGUGCCUGGCAGAAUGCCCUGCCUGCCUGCCUGCCAGGCCAAGGCCUGCGUCUCUCUGCUGUACCAGCUCUGUUCCAGGGCCUCCUCAGGCUCGUUACCCCUGUGCCUGUGUCUCUACACACUCCACACCCCCUCAAACUCUGUUUAUCUGUUCUCUGACCUUGUGUCCCCUGCGCUGGGACCCUUCCUCCUGAGGCCCAGGUCUUUGUCCCCAGUUGUGUGCCUUGACCUCUCUCGCCCCUUUCUGGGUGUGUUCGCACAUCCUGUGUGUGCACAGCUGUCCCUCCACUGGAUCCCCUUCACACGUGACCCGUGGGGCAGCCAGUCCUCCCAGGGACUACAUAACAGGCACCUUUGAGAGAGCAUGGGAGAAGGUGGAUAAGAGGAUGCUGCUCAGUGCUUUUCUCUUCCACUUUCCUGCCACUCCCCACUACCCUCGGAGAGAGGUGGUGGGAUGGGAGAGAGCCCCUGUGAAAGCCUGUGAGGAUCUGAAGAGUAAAGGGCUGGGUCUGCCUCAGAAGGCACCAGCACCAGGGCCCAGGUAUUAAGGCUGAGAGUGAAGGCUGCCAAUGUCAGCUUUGGAGGUCCCAGAAGUCUUCUGUUCUCUGGCCUCACCCCCUCAGUCGCCAUAGAGCUGGGCCUGGCCUUGCUGGAAUGGAGGCAUCCUUCCAAACCUGGGGGACGGGGGUGGGGGGUGGUAGUGGUGGGAGGGAAACCAUGUCUUGCUAAACCUGUUUCUGGUGCCUCCCAUCCCCAGACCCACCAGACACCACACAGCAGACAAUACACACCCACUCGCACAAGCUUCCAUCCACAUGUGUUGUACUUUCAGCUCUAGGCAUGCAGACAACCCCACACGGCCACACCACCACAUGCCCAAGUGUACACACACAGAGCCACACCGUCCCUCUGGGCCUGCUGGCUCCUCCCUUGGCUUUCCCUUGGCCCACUUCCAGGGCCCAGGUGCUGCAACUAAAUGUGAAAGCUCAGUGGCCGCUCCUUCUUUCAGCCCAUCAACCAGCAUUGGUCCCAUAGGGAAGCACAGGGGACUCACCCUCUUUCAUAUCCCUUGCCCUGCCCUGAAAUGGACAAUCACUUUUUGGGAUAGGUUGAAAUUUUUAAAGAGCCUGCAUCAUUUGGUUCCCUCAAAGGGAAGCCCUUGCCAGUGGGGGUUUGAAAGAGAAUUUUUGGAACCAACAUUCAAAUUCUGCCUCAUCUGGAGGGAAACCAAAAUUGGGAGGGGGAAGAGGACCCCUGAUGUUUUGCUGCUUCCAGAGAUAUUAGAAACUGACUCACUUGAUUGGAAAAUGGACAAAAGUGCCUUGACGUGGAGGGUGGGCACCAGAUGGGGACCAGCCUUGCCAACUGCUGCUGUGGCCUCCAGCUUGGCUGGUUUUGCAGGCCGCCAGCAGGAAGGCGAAGGUGGUAGUACAGCAAGAGGCACUGGCGGGGCAGCAGGCCUGCAGGAGCUGUUUUUCCAUUGCUAGGCCUGACCCCUCUCUACCUGUGAGCGUUCAGGGGGUCCCUGAGAUAGUUUAGAUGCCCCCCCAUCUUAGACCUCAGCUCCCACAGUGCCUUUUAAGGGGGACCUCACCUCCUGUGCACAGCCCACCCACUUUCCUCUGCUUCCCUGGCACAGCCCAGGCAUAGACGAGCUGGCGUUGGACCCAGUUCUUCCCCCUUUUCAGCCCCACAGCUGCUGCCACAGGGGCCAACUAGGGCCAGGUGGAAGGGGAGCUGAGAAGCCAACCCCUAGCCCAGGGGUGCUGUGGGAACUGGGAUCCAAUUUGUAGCUUCCUGCCUGGCUUCAGAGAGCCCAGCAACCUUCUAGGCCUGCUUUCCAGACUUCUGAGAUAGCCUGGGAUGAGCAAUCCUGUUAUAGUACAUCUGGACCUUCCCUACCUGGGCUCUGGGGAGGCUGUGGGCCUGGAGAGGGAAAAGGAGGGAGGGGGUGUCUGCACCACCUGGGAAGAUAGCACAAGGCCUAAUGAGGUCACCCUGACUCCCCACCCCAGCAUUUCAUUCAUACCAGAUAAUAGCUGCAUUACUGCCAACUGACCUUAUAACCCUCUGCACCUUCAAAAAGAUUCAUGGUUUUUAAUUGCUGCUUUUAAUAACAUUUGUUAAAGUUAUAAUUAAUGUGUCUGAUUUAUGAUUUAAAACCUCCCUUUGAACAAUCA